ACGGCCGGAGCUGUUUGUGCUGGGAGCUGGUGGCGCGGUGCAGGGCUCUUAAGAACGAACGGCUUGGGCGCGGACUGGUAUCCGGGGACUGUGACUUGCAGGGUCCGCCAUGGAGCCAGAGCAGAUGCUGGAGGGACAAACGCAGGUUGCAGAAAAUCCUCACUCUGAGUACGGUCUCACAGACAACGUUGAGAGAAUAGUAGAAAAUGAGAAGAUUAAUGCAGAAAAGUCAUCAAAGCAGAAGGUAGAUCUCCAGUCUUUGCCAACUCGUGCCUACCUGGAUCAGACAGUUGUGCCUAUCUUAUUACAGGGACUUGCUGUGCUUGCAAAGGAAAGAGUUUUACAACAGAGAGAAAAUACAGCAGUCAAGUAUAAUUUAAAAAAUUCAGCCAAUUUUUCUCAGCAUUGUUUCUGGACCUUUCUGAGGGUGGGAUCUGGGCAUCUUCAAUGGCUUAACAAGUAUCACAGAUGAGGAAACAGACUUGGAGAGGUUAAGUGACAUGCUCAAGACAACACUGCUGGCUGGAGUGCAAUGGCAUGAUCUCGGCUCACAGCAACCUCUGCCUCCCAGGUUCAAGCGAUUCUCCUGCCUCAGCCUCCCGAGUUGCUGGGAUUACAGGCACCUGCCACCACGCCUGGCUAAUUUUUGUAUUUUUAGUGGAGAUGGGGUUUUGCCCUUUUGGCCAGGCUGGUCUCAAACUCUUGGCCACGUGAUCCGCCCGCCUUGGCCUCCCAAAGUGCUGGGAUUACAGGCAGGAGCCACCGCGCCCGGCCUGCCUUCUUAUUUCUUGAAGUCUGAGCUUCAUAAGGAUUGUCUGUUAAUAAAAGUUUCCUCCUUGCUCCCUACUAUGAAUAAUGCUUAUGCAGUGUCAAACCAAAAUCACUAGUGGAUAUAAUGGAAAUUAUUGAUAAUAACAUGAAAAUUGUACAGUAUUGCCAGAUAAGCUUCUCCUAAAAUACAAAGUAUUUUGCAUUAUAUGAAUUUUCCUUAAUUUAGGGGAGGUGAAUAAAUGAAUAGUUUCAACCUCUUUCAAGGGUAUACUUGAGUAAGGUAGCUAGAAUAAGGUGGACAGGGGGAAUAAUUGUGGCACGUAUUGAGAGCAUCCUAGAGAUAACAUAAUUAUCUGCUAACCUUUCAGUUCAAUUGCAUUGUGAUCUUUAUUCAGUUUGACCAGCAAGAAAAUUUCAGUAGAGCAUUUUAAUAGGGAGAAAGCUGAAUUUUAAAUUAGAUUACUAGUUUGGAAUGAGACUUACGAUUGUUGCUAGGAGUAGAGGAUAAUAAUAAGAACAAAUAUUUAUAAAGAACAGCUUAUGAAGCAUUUUAACAUACCUUAAUAAUUCUCACAGCAAGCAUAUGAGUUAGCUAUUACUCCUGUUUGCAUUUGACAGAUAACACUGAGGCUAGAAAAGGUUAAAUUACUAGAUGUCCAUGGUCACACAGCUGAUGAGUGACAGGGCCAGGACUCAAAUCUGACUUUCUAAUUUGAAGGGCCUGAAAUACUAAGCUUUCUUUGUUUAAUUGUAUCCAAUCCCCUCUCCACCACCCCACAACACCCCACACCUCUUUUCCAUAGAAACAAAAUCAGCAAUAAAUAACCAUAAGAACCAUCAUCAUAUAAACACUUAGGGCAGUUUCCUUUUCUUGCAACUUACAACAAAACUUUACCAUUUUAUCAAUGAUCACUGAGUUUUGGUACUGUCAGAACAGUACCAUGUAAUCAGAGCUCAAGCCUUCUUUUUUCUGUUACCUCUAAAGUAGCUUUGGCCUGGGUGCGAUGGCUCAUGCCUGUAAUCCCAGCACUUUGGGAGGCCGAGGCCGGUGGAUCACCUGAGGUUAGGAGUUCAAGACCACCCUGGCCAACAUGGUGAAACCCUGUCUCUACUAAAAAUACAAAAAUUAGCUGGGCAUGGUGGAUGGUGGUGGGCACCCAUGAUCCCAGCUACUCUGGAGGCUGAGGCAAGAGAAUCACUUGAACUCGGGAGGCGGAGGUUGCAGCGAGCCCAGAUCGAGCCACUGCACUCCAGCCUGGGUGACAGAGCAAGACUCUGUCUCAAAAAAAAAAAAAAAAAAAAAAAAAAAAAGAAAAAAGAGAGAGGUUUUGGAUACAUGGUAUGUCCAUUUUUUUUUUGUUGCAUAUUAUGUUUUGUGCAAGUUGGUGGAGAGGGUAAAAUUUGAGUAAACAAAUAUACAGUGGAGAUUUUAGCCUAAUUAGAAAAAGGUAUGAGAGUCAGAAGUGUUCCAGUAAUUGACUAGGCUUUAGGACAGGGAUACUGCACAAAAUCCUUGGGCCCUGAAGUUGGAGAAGGUGGGAGGAGGAGAGGAAACAGAAUAGCACUUUUAAAAGUAAACUUGAAUACUAGACAGCCAGUCAUCUACUCUGGAAUCUGUCAGGGGCUUGUUUAGUAUGAAACUCAGAUAUAAUUUUUUUUCUUUUCUUUUUUGAGACAGGGUCUUGCUACGUACGUUGCCCAGGUUGGAAUGCAGUGGCGUGAUCAUGGCUCACUGUAGCCUCGACCUCCUGGGCUCAAGUGAUCCUCCCGCCUCCGCCUACCAAGUAGCUAGGACCACAGGCGAAGCCACCACGCCCGGAUAAUUAAAAAAUAAAAAAUUCAUAGAAACAGGGUCUCCUAUGUUCCCCAGGCUGGUCUAGAACUCCUGGCCUCAGGCAGUCCUACUGCCUCAGGCCCCCAAAGUGCUGGGAUUAUAGGCAGGAGGUACCAUGCCCAUGCAGUUACAAACAUUUUAUAGUGUUUGCCCCAAAACUUUCAUUGGAUGUAUGCAACUUUCUCUUCCUCUAUUCCUACUUUUGCAAUGGUGUACUUUGUAACAAUAACACUUCCUCAGAGGUCCAA